ACUGUGCAUCCAGGCACGGAGGAUGUUGCAUUCCUGCCGUCACCUUUGUCGCUGCGAGGGCGGCGGUUGGGAUCUGGCCUUUCCAGCCCCGAGAGGGACCUAGUGCCUCUACCCAGAUUUCUGUCGCUCUGUCACCUGCGCUAUGCCCUGCUUUACUCACAGGAGCUGUAGAGAGGACCCCGGUACAUCUGAAAGCCGGGAAAUGGUGCUACAGACCCACAGUCCAAGGAGACAUUAGGGACAGCCCAAGCAGCUGACAGAGCGAUACACUAUCACAAAAAAAAAAAAAAAAAAAAAAAAAAAAUUGCUGUCUGGGUGUGGUGGCUCAUGCCUGUAAUCCUAGCACUUUGUGACUCUGAGGCAGGUGGAUCACCUGAGGUUGGGAGUUCGAGACCAGCCUGACCAACAUGGAGAAACCCUGUCUCUACUAAAAAUACAAAAUUAGCCGGGUAUGCUGGUGCAUGCCUGUAAUCCCAGCUACUCGGGAGGCUGAGGCAGAAGAAGCACUUGAACCCCGGCAGUGAGCCGAGAUUGCACCAUUGUACUCCAGCCUGGGCAAUAAGAGUGAAAUUCUGUCUCAAAAAAAUAAAAAAAAAAAUUGCUUUAUGGAAGAAAGUAAGUAUAGACAGAGAGAAAGGGAUCUGAUGACCAAAGCAGGGAAUAAAUGUUUGGAGUCCACGGCAUCCUGAGAACUUCUUGGGAAUAGAGUCUAGGCCCCCAAUGCUGUCACUCUCACCCAUCCUCCUCUACACAUGUGAGAUGUUUCAGGACCCAGUGGCUUUUAAGGAUGUGGCUGUGAACUUCACCCAGGAGGAGUGGGCUUUGCUGGAUAUUUCCCAGAAGAAUCUCUACAGGGAAGUGAUGCUGGAAACUUUCUGGAACCUGACCUCUAUAGGAAAAAAGUGGAAAGACCAGAACAUUGAAUAUGAGUACCAAAACCCCAGGAGAAACUUCAGGAGUGUCACAGAAGAGAAAGUCAAUGAAAUUAAAGAAGACAGUCAUUGUGGAGAAACUUUUACCCCAGUUCCAGAUGACAGGCUGAACUUCCAGAAGAAGAAAGCUUCUCCUGAAGUAAAAUCAUGUGACAGCUUUGUGUGUGAAGUUGGCCUAGGUAACUCAUCUUCUAAUAUGAACAUCAGAGGUGACACUGGACACAAGGCAUGUGAAUGUCAGGAAUAUGGACCAAAGCCAUGGAAGAGUCAACAACCUAAAAAAGCCUUCAGAUAUCACCCCUCCUUGAGAACACAAGAAAGGGAUCACACUGGAAAGAAACCCUAUGCUUGUAAAGAAUGUGGAAAAAACAUUAUUUACCAUUCAAGCAUUCAAAGACACAUGGUAGUGCACAGUGGGGAUGGACCUUAUAAAUGUAAGUUUUGUGGGAAAGCAUUCCAUUGUCUCAGUUUAUAUCUUAUCCAUGAAAGAACUCACACUGGAGAGAAACCGUAUGAAUGUAAACAAUGUGGUAAAUCUUUUAGUUAUUCUGCUACCCAUCGAAUACAUGAAAGAACUCACAUUGGAGAAAAGCCUUAUGAAUGUCAGGAAUGUGGGAAAGCAUUCCAUAGUCCCAGAUCCUGUCACAGACAUGAAAGGAGUCACAUGGGAGAGAAGGCUUAUCAAUGUAAGGAAUGUGGAAAAGCAUUCAUGUGUCCCCGUUAUGUUCGUAGACAUGAAAGGACCCACUCUAGGAAAAAACUUUAUGAAUGUAAGCAGUGUGGGAAAGCAUUAUCCUCUCUUACAAGUUUUCAAACACACAUAAGAAUGCACUCUGGAGAAAGACCUUAUGAAUGUAAGACAUGUGGGAAAGGCUUUUAUUCUGCCAAGUCAUUUCAAAGACAUGAAAAAACUCACAGUGGAGAGAAACCGUAUAAAUGCAAGCAAUGUGGUAAAGCCUUCACUCGUUCCGGUUCCUUUCGAUAUCAUGAAAGGACUCACACUGGAGAGAAACCCUAUGAGUGUAAGCAAUGUGGGAAAGCCUUCAGAUCUGCCCCAAAUCUUCAAUUGCAUGGUAGGACUCACACUGGAGAGAAACCGUAUCAAUGUAAGGAAUGUGGGAAAGCUUUCAGAUCUGCCUCACAACUUCGAAUCCAUCGUAGGAUUCACACUGGAGAGAAACCCUAUGAAUGUAAGAAAUGUGGGAAAGCCUUCAGAUAUGUCCAGAACUUUCGAUUUCAUGAAAGGACACAAACACAUAAGAAUGCACUCUGGAGAAAGACCUUAUAAAUAUAAGAUAUAUGGGAAACACUUUUAUUCUGCCAAGUUAUUUCAAACACAUGAAAAAAUUCACACUGGAGAGAAACCCUAUAAAUGCAAGCAAUGUGGUAAAGCCUUAAUUGUUCCAGUUCCUUUCGAUAUCUAAAAGGACUCACAGUGGAGAAAAACUCUAUGAGUGUAAGCAAUGUGGGAAAGUCUUCAGAUCUGUCAAGAACCUUUCAAUUUAUGAAAGGACACACACUGGAGAGAAACCCUAUGAAUGUAAGAAAUGUGGAAAAGCGUUCCAUAAUUUCUCUUCUUUUCAAAUACAUGAAAGUUGCACAGAGGAGAGGCGCCCUAAGAAUGUAAGCAUUGUGGGAAAGCAUUCAUAUCUGCCAAGAUCGUUUGAAUACAUGCAAAACACACACUGGAGAGAAACCUAUGAAUGUAAGGAAUGCAAACAAGCAUUCAAUUAUUUUUCUUCCUUGCAUAUACAUGAAAGGACUCAUACGAGAGAGAAUCCGUAUGAAUGUAAGGAUUGUGGGAAAGCAUUCAGCUUGCUUAAUUGCUUUCAUAGACAUGUAAAGACACACCAGAAGGAAACCCUAUGAAUGUAAGCAAUGUGGCAAAAGCUUUCACUUCUUCCAGUUCUUUUCAAUAUCAUGAAAGGACUCACACUGGGGAGAAACCGUAUCAAUGUAAGCAAUGUGGGAAAGCCGUCAGAUCAGCCUCAAGACUUCAAAUGCAUGGAAGCACUCACACUUGGCAGAAACUCUAUGAAUGUAAGCAGUAUGGGAAAGCCUUCAGAUCGGCUAGGAUUCUUUGAAUACAAAUAAUGAAUGUAAACAAUUAACUGUUUAUAAUAACUGUAUACUAACAAAUGUUAUUCUUUUUAAAUAAUUAAGAAGCUAUAAUAAAAUAUCCAUUGGUGUCAUGUAUUAGAUCAA